ACUCGCGUCCCUGCGCCGUGCCUGCCUCGCGCUCCCUGUUACGGCGUUCGUCCCCGGGCCUGGCGCCCGCGUCCGGCCCGGCUCCGCGGCGGCCUGGUCCGAUGGCUCCUCAGCGGAGGGCCGCAACCAAGGCGCCCGAGGGCAACGGAGCGGCCGAGCGCCGGAACCGGAGCAGCACCAAGAAGGACCGAGCCCCGCGGGAGGUGCAGAGGCUGUGGCAGAGGCCGUGGCUAAGGACCGCGGGCCUGGGGGCUGGCUUUGUGCUCACCGCACUCCUGCUCUGGAGCAGCUUGGGGGCCGACGACGGGGUCGCAGAGGUCCUGGCCCGCCGUGGCGAGGUCGUGGCAGGGAGAUUCAUCGAGGUGCCCUGCUCUGAGGACUACGACAGUCACCGCAGGUUCGAAGGCUGCACUCCCCGAAAGUGCGGCAGAGGUGUCACCGAUGUCGUCAUCACCAGGGAGGAAGCGGAGCGGAUUCGCAGCGUAGCUGAAAAGGGGCUCUCCCUGGGAGGAUCUGACGGAGGGGCAUCCAUUCUGGACUUGCACUCAGGGGCCCUGUCUGUCGGGAAGCACUUUGUGAACCUGUACAGAUACUUCGGGGAUAAAAUACAGAACAUCUUCUCAGAGGAGGACUUCCGGUUAUACCGGGAGGUGCGGCAGAAGGUCCAGCUCACCAUUGCUGAGGCUUUUGGCAUCAGCGCAUCCUCGCUGCAUCUGACCAAGCCCACCUUCUUCUCCCGCAUAAACAGCACGGAAGCGCGGACGGCGCACGACGAGUACUGGCAUGCGCACGUGGACAAGGUGACCUACGGCUCCUUCGACUACACCUCGCUGCUGUACCUCUCCAACUACCUGGAGGACUUCGGCGGAGGGCGGUUCAUGUUCAUGGAGGAGGGUGCCAACAAGACGGUGGAGCCGAGAGCUGGAUGUUUUUGUUUCCGGAUGAUGUCUUGUGGGUUCCAAGAAGUUAAUGGACCGAGAGCCAGUGAAGCUGCUGGUGCGAAGGCUGGAGUCAGGUGUCCUCCGGGGACUCACCACCCGCCCGAGAGGGGAGAGACACAUGCGAUUCUGGAAGCUGAGAGCAUUGCUUAUUGUUGAUUCCUUGGUUGCCGUGCUGAGUCCUGCUUUAAGGAAGCAGGUCGCGUCUCCUUCUUCACCUCGGGGUCCGAGAACCUACACCGCGUGGAGAAGGUCCACUGGGGCACCCGUUACGCCAUCACCAUCGCCUUCAGCUGCAACCCCGACCAUGGCAUCGAGGACCCAGCGUUCCCGUAGCCAGCAGCCGGGCCAAGGUAACUUCAGGAGGGCCCGUGUGGAGGCAGCCGCGCCAGUCGUGCACCCACCCCCACGUCCACCCGCUCCUGUUGCACAGAGUGCCUUAGGAAUUCUCUGAUUUUGAUUUGCUGACGUGUUAAUCUUUUCAUCUGUGAGUAAAUGAAGGGAACCAGCUUUUCACUUCUCCAGCAUCAUGUGUGCUUGGGCUGUAGGCCUGGGAGCCUGAGGUGGAGGCCAGGAAAGGGACCCAGCAGGACGGGGCACAAGUCCCCAUCUGUGAAUGGACGGGACUCAUCCACCCAGGUUCAGCAACCCCCCGGGACUCGUCCAGGUUCAGCAACCCCCCGGCCCAUCAAAGACUGGCUAAAGCAUCAGCCAUAAAUGGGGACAAACGUGGGGCCAGCAGCUUCUGUUCGGGGUCUCGGCAUCAGCAAACCGCAGCAGCUUUGGAGAAGGGUCCGUGAGUGGCGGCUCUGGAGGCAGCAACGGGGUCCUUUGGGGUGGGUGGGAGUUCUGCUGGAUUCAGGUGGAGGUGAACAUCUGCCGUUCCCACAGCCCUGCGUGCACCCCCAAUGCUGCUGGCCCACAAAUCACCGUGGGCCACGGCCCCACCACACCAGGCUUGGCCCUGUCAGCGGCCAGCAUCCCAAGGGCCAGGGUCCGAGUGUCCUCACCAAGGAGGCUCUUGGCGUCGCUGUGCCGGCUCCCAUGGGCCUUCUGCUGGGUCGAGGGUAGGUCUCCUCCUCCCCCUUUGCCCUGGCAUUAAACUGAUGGUCAGGCUGGGCGCGGUGGCUCACACCUGUAAUCUCAGCACUGCGGGAGGCCGAGGCAGGAGGAUCACUUGAGGUCAGGAGUUCAAGACCAGCCUGGCCAACAUGGCGAAACCCUGUCUCUACUAAAAACACAAAAACAAAUUAAUCCCAGCUACUGGGGAGGCUGAGGCAGGAGAAUCGCUUGAACCCAGGGGGCAGAAGUUGCAGUGAGCCGAGAUCGUGCCACUACACUCCAGCCUGGGUGACAGAGUGAGACUCCAUCUUAAAAAUAUAAAAAUAAAGUGGUGGUCAGAGGAGCCCCGAAUAGACCAGUUGUGGAGAGGCCUGGGUGGGGUGGCUGGCAGGGAGGGCAGGCCAAGCCCAGUUUCUGCCCACAGUCACCUCGAGGUGACUGUCCAGGGCUUUGGGCACCUUCCCGGGAGGGGGACGGCCGCCCACCCUGAGUGGUGUUGGAAGCUGGGCUCUCCUGGAUGCCCUGACCCAGCUGCCUGGGGAGAGCCCUGGGCCCCUCCUCCCUCAGCACCUCCUCCCUCAGCCCCUCCUGCCUCGGUCCCUCCUCCCUUAGCCUGUCUGGCAUAGAUCCAUGUUCCCUAGCCCCUGGCACAGGUGCCUCUGACUGGAGGAGGCCCCACCUGUGGCCCGGGAGCUGCUCUGGGGGUUGAUAAAGGGCAGCAUUAUUGGGUCCUGGGAAGGAGCGGGCGUGAGGCCAGCUGAGGCAUGGUGACCCCUGGGAAGGAGCGGGCGUGAGGCCAGCUGAGGCAUGGUGACCCCUGGGAAGGAGCGGGCGUGAGGCCAGCUGAGGCAUGGUGACCCCUGGGAAGGAGCGGGCGUGAGGCCAGCUGAGGCAUGGUGACCCCUGGGAAGGAGCGGGCGUGAGGCCAGCUGAGGCAUGGUGACCCCUGGGUACGGGGGACUUGGGGGCCGCACCUUGGUUUGCCCAGGGCCCCUCCUGCACCACGGGCCACAUGCGGAGGACGGCGUGGGAUAGGCUCCCUGGGUCCACAGCUUCUGCCCGUGUAUGGGGAACCCUCCUUGGUCAGGGCUGCAGGCUCUGGGCAGAUGGGGCAGGAACCCUGAGGCUCCCGCGCCCUCCCAUGGCCUCUGAUGUGGGACACUGGAGCGAGGCACGAUUCUGAAGGACUCCAUGGAUCUGGGAGGAUGAGGCCCACCUCCGGUUGGUGGCCAAAGCCGUCCUUGCGGGGCCGGCUGCUUCACGGACACUCUCCGGGUCGGGCUGGUGGGCCCCAUCGUGGGUGGGAAGUCGCCUGAGCCUGGGCCGCCCUUGAGCUUCUCCCAGUCUUGACUUUCCAGAGGGUCCGUGGCUGUGGUCAUGGUCGGGGCAGGUGGAAAAUGCUGCAUGGAAACCUGAUCCUGUCACCUUGGAGUAAAUGAUGAUGUCGCCGGCUUCUCGCCACGUCUAAAGGAUAAAUGCAUUUGAAGAAAGUGGGUGUUGGGUUUGUUAUGGGUUAAAGUGCUUUUGAAAUAAGUAAAUUAUUAGUUUGAUUUUCAUUCUUGGCUACUUACACUAUUCAUGAUAAUCACAGAGAUACUUGGACAAAGAAAUAUAUUUGGGCAAAAGCAAGAAUUUCCUUCUUUUUUUUUUUGAGACGGAGUCUAACUCUGUCGCCCAGGCUGGAGUGCAGUGGCGCAAUCUCGGCUCACUGCAAGGUCCACCUCCUGGGUUCCCACCAUUCUCCUGCCUCAACCUCCCGAGUAGCUGGGACUACAGGCGCCCGCCACCAUGCCCGGCUAAUUUUUUUUGUAUUUUUAGUAGAGAUGGGAUUUCACCGUGUUAGCCAGAAUGAAGAAUUUCCUUCUGAAGUGGGAACAUAUGGCUCAUGCUGGUAAUCCCAGCACUUUGGGAGGCCAAGGUAGGAAGAUCACUUGAGCCCAGGAGUUGGAGACCCAUCUGUGCAACAUAGUGAGACGCUGUCUGUACAAGAAACUUUUAAAAAAUGUAGCUGGGCGUGGCAGUGUGCUCCUGUGGUCCCAGCUACUCGGAGCUGAGGCAGGACGACUGCUUGAGCCCAGGAGGUCGAGGCUACAGUGAGCUGUGACGGCUCCACUGCAUUCCAGCCUGGGAGACAGCAAGAUACUGUCUCAAAAAAAAAUUUAUCAUUGAAGCCUGGGCAUUUUAAAAAAAUAAAAAGGUGGGAAAAUACGUGGGCACAGCAGUGAAUCCUCACACCCUGGGCUUUGCCCAAGAAGUGCUCGUGAACCUGAUGAAAGUGUCGGGUGUGGCCGACGUGAGGCUGUUCCAGGAGCCACGAGGGGUGAUUGGUUCCGCUAGAAGGUUCCAGGGAGGAACUGGAGUCUCAGGUGUGUCCUCUGAUGAGUGAUCUAUUUUUAAGUAAAAGUGUUUCAUUAAAGUCAAAGAUGAUUAUUCCUUUCAAAAUAAAGAAUCUAGGAGGGCGA